AUACUCUGAGCCCUGCUCGGUUUAGGCCUGUCUGCGGAAUCCGCACCAACCAGCACCAUGCCCAUGAUACUGGGGUACUGGGACAUCCGCGGGACAAAGUCAGGGACCCUCCAUCUCUGACGCGACCUGCGGGCCAUCUCUCCCAGCUGGCCCACGCCAUCCGCCUGCUCCUGGAAUACACAGACUCAAGCUAUGAGGAAAAGAAGUACACGAUGGGGGACGCUCCUGAUUAUGACAGAAGCCAGUGGCUGAAUGAAAAAUUCAAGCUGGGCCUGGACUUUCCCAAUCUGCCCUACUUGAUUGAUGGGGCUCACAAGAUCACCCAGAGCAACGCCAUCUUGUGCUACAUUGCCCGCAAGCACAACCUGUGUGGGGAGACAGAAGAGGAGAAGAUUCGUGUGGACAUUUUGGAGAACCAGACCAUGGACAACCAUAUGCAGCUGGGCAUGAUCUGCUACAAUCCAGAAUUUGAGAAACUGAAGCCAAAGUACUUGGAGGAACUCCCUGAAAAGCUAAAGCUCUACUCAGAGUUUCUGGGGAAGCGGCCAUGGUUUGCAGGAAACAAGAUCACUUUUGUAGAUUUUCUCGUCUAUGAUGUCCUUGACCUCCACCGUAUAUUUGAGCCCAAGUGCUUGGACGCCUUCCCAAAUCUGAAGGACUUCAUCUCCCGCUUUGAGGGCUUGGAGAAGAUCUCUGCCUACAUGAAGUCCAGCCGCUUCCUCCCAAGACCUGUGUUCUCAAAGAUGGCUGUCUGGGGCAACAAGUAGGGCCUUGAAGGCCAGGAGGUGGGAGUGAGGAGCCCAUACUCAGCCUGCUGCCCAGGCUGUGCAGCGCAGCUGGACUCUGCAUCCCAGCACCUGCCUCCUCGUUCCUUUCUCCUGUUUAUUCCCAUCUUUACUCCCAAGACUUCAUUGUCCCUCUUCACUCCCCCUAAACCCCUGUCCCAUGCAGGCCCUUUGAAGCCUCAGCUACCCACUAUCCUUCGUGAACAUCCCCUCCCAUCAUUACCCUUCCCUGCACUAAAGCCAGCCUGACCUUCCUUCCUGUUAGUGGUUGUGUCUGCUUUAAAGGGCCUGCCUGGCCCCUCGCCUGUGGAGCUCAGCCCCGAGCUGUCCCCGUGUUGCAUGAAGGAGCAGCAUUGACUGGUUUACAGGCCCUGCUCCUGCAGCAUGGUCCCUGCCUUAGGCCUACCUGAUGGAAGUAAAGCCUCAACCACA